GAGGGUUCCCCUGGUCUUAAAAGGGGCCCAAGCCCCCAUUCUGGCACACCCCACUCCACUGUCCUGGCAGCAGCAGGUGUGGCCAAUGGAGGGGGGUGCUGGCCCCCAGGAUUCCCCCAGCCAAACUGUCUUUGUCACCACGUGAGGCUCACACCUUUCAUCCUUCCCCACCUUCCCUAGUCCCUGCACUAGGUUGGACAGCCCCCAUUGGCUACAGGAAAGCGGGAGGGGUGUGAGUCCCCUACUCCCUCUUUGCAGUGGCCCCAGCCCCCUUACCGUCUGCCUGGGAUCUGAGUACAUAUUGCAGUGAUGGAGAUGCAGUCACCUAUUGUCCAGAGGCAGGAGAGGCAGGUCCGAGACCGCGGGGUGACCCGGUCCAAGGCGGAAAAAGUGCGGCCGCCCACUGUGCCAGUGCCGCAGGUGGAUAUUGUGCCUGGGCGGCUCAGUGAGGCCGAGUGGAUGGCGCUUACAGCCCUCGAGGAGGGCGAGGACGUCGUAGGGGACAUCUUGGCCGACUUGCUGGCUCGAGUCAUGGACUCUGCUUUCAAAGUCUACCUGACUCAGCAGUGCAUUCCAUUCACCAUCAGCCAGGCCCGGGAGGCCAUGCUGCAGAUCACCGAGUGGCGCUUCCUGGCCCGGGACGAGGGAGAAUCUGCAGUAGCUGAGGACCCCACAUGGGGUGAGGACGAGGAGCCUUCGGCAUGCACGACGGACUCCUGGGCUCAGGGUUCAGUGCCCGUGCUGCACGCGUCCACCUCGGAGGGCCUGGAGAACUUCCAAGGCGAAGACCCUGGGGGCGUGGACCGGAUCCCUUUAGGAAGGUCGUGGAUGGGUCGAGGCUCCCAGGAGCAGAUGGAAUCUUGGGAGCCUUCUCCGCAGCUGAGAGUCACGUCGGCCCCUCCUCCCACAUCAGAGCUGUUUCAGGAGGCAGGGCCCGGAGGUCCUGUAGAGGAAGCGGACGGCCAGUCUAGAGGCCUCUCCUCGGCCGGGUCCUUGAGCGCGAGCUUCCAACUGUCGGUGGAGGAGGCGCCUGCCGACGAUGCCGACCCUUCUCUGGAUCCGUACCUGGUAGCCAGCCCCCAGGCCUCAACUGGGAGGGGACACCCCCUCGGCUUCCAUUUGUCGUUGGAAGACCUCUACUGUUGCAUGCCUCAACUGGACGCGGCUGGGGAUCGGCUGGAACUCAGGUCAGAGGGGGUGCCCUGCAUCGCCUCGGGCGUGUUGGUGUCCUACCCCUCUGUGGGCGGCGCCACCCGCCCCUCCGCGUCCUGCCAGCAGCAGCGGGCCGGGCACUCGGAUGUGCGGCUGAGCGCCCACCACCACAGGAUGCGCCGCAAGGCGGCCGUGAAACGCCUGGACCCUGCGAGGCUCCCGUGCCACUGGGUGCGCCCUCUGGCUGAGGUCCUGGUCCCAGACUCUCAAACACGCCCCUUGGAAGCCUACCGCGGACGCCAGCGGGGCGAGAAGACCAAGGCCCGGGCCGAACCCCAAGCCCUCGGCCCCGGCACCCGUGUCUCCCCGGCAGCGUUCUUCCCUCUCCGGCCAGGCAUUCCUUUCCGUGACUUGGACUCGGGCCCCGCACUCCUGUUCCCCACUUUAAAUUUAGGCCUAUCGUCGCCAUCCCUCGAGUCAAAGCUGCCACUCCCAAACUCCAGGAUCCGCUUCCUCACCACACACCCGGUGCUCCCUGAUGUGGCCCGCAGCCGCAGCCCCAAGCUGUGGCCCAGUGUCAGGUGGCCCAGCGGUUGGGAGGGGAAGGCCGAGCUGCUGGGCGAGCUGUGGGCUGGCCGGACCCGCGUGCCUCCACAGGGUCUGGAGCUGGCAGACAGGGAGGGCCAGGAUCCUGGCAGAUGGCCUCGAACCACACCCCCGGUCCUUGAAGCCACUUCCCAGGUGAUGUGGAAGCCCGUGUUGCUGCCAGAAGCCCUGAAGCUGGCCCCUGGUGUGAGCAUGUGGAACCGGAGCACCCAGGUGUUGCUCAGCUCUGGUGUGCCUGAACAAGAGGACAAAGAAGGUAGCACCUUUCCUCCCGUUGAGCAACAUCCCAUCCAGACAGGUGCCCCAAAGCCCAGGUGACCGUAGCACAGCUAAUGAAGAACUCAGCCCCCAAAGUGUGGUCACGCUCCUCUAAGCCUGCUGCCUCCCUCUGAUCCCUGAGCCUCUGGCAGUAGUAACUGGUCCCUCCCUCUGCUAGCCAGAAAUAAACACCUGAGUUGCCUUAGGAACUA